GAGGAGGAAUACUUCCAAACUCAUUUUAUGAAGCCAGCAUUACACUGAUACAAAAACCAGAGAUGGACAUUACAAGAAAAACAAUUACAGGCCAAUAUCCCUGAUGAACAUAGAUGAAAAAUCAUCCGCAACGUAGUUGCAAAUGAAAUUCAAAAGCACUUUAAAAGGAUCAUUUAUUAUGAUCAAGUUGGAUUUAUUCCUGGGAUGCAAUAAUAUUUUAAUAUGUGGAAAUCAAUAAAUGCCAUACUCCUUAUUUACACAACAAAAAGAUUAAAAAUCAUGACUUUUUUAUGCAUGCCUAAAAUUAUUUUGACAAAAUUUAAAAUCCAUUCCAAAUAAAAUCUAUAACAAAUUAGGUAUAGAAAGAAUAUACCUCAAAAUAAAGAGAUAUGUUCUUUAUAAGCUAUAGGACAAUCCCAUGGUUAACAUUAUUGUCAAUGGUGAAAUUUUGGAAUUGUUUUUAAGAUUUAUUAUAAGAAAAAGAUGCCCACUCUCACUACUUCUUUCAACACCGUAUUGGAAAUCCUGCUCAGAAUCUAAGACAAGAGAAAAAAGAGCAUUUAAAUAAGAAACAACAAGUUCUUCUAUUCAUGGAGAUUAACGCUCAGGUUUUUGCAGAUUAGAUUUAACAGCAUGAAAUCUGUACCAUCCAGGAAUCAAAGGAUAUAGGACUUUAGGGCAUCAAUUAUUAAGAGGCUAUAGGAAAGCAGAAAUGCUCCUGGAUGUUUCCAUUGUCCACACACAAAAUUUCAACAGACCAGCCCCAGGAAGUAAAGGCACAUUCCUGACUACUGUUAGUUGAUGAGCUUUUCACCAAAAGCAGAGAUGUGAGACCUGGCAGGUUUCAAAGACCCCUCAAGUGCUCCAUACCUUGAAAUUCACUUCCACAAAGCUAGAACACCAUCUGUUCCUGAGGGAUCAGGUUAUCGUCUGUUUCUUUUAGGCACUGGCCAGUCAGGCUUUAGUGGACACGAAGCCACAGAUUUUUAGUGUAAAAUGCCUAAUCUAUCAUAAUCUUUAGGUAGAUAUUUGGAGGCCUGCACACUUAAAUGGGUUGGUGAAAUGUCAUACCAGACACAUGGCUGGGAAUUGGGUUUUUCUCCUCCGCUCUUAGCAGCACCUUUGUAACCCAGUGAUUACCCCCCUCAUGGCUCCACGGCCACAUCCGCAAAAAGGGUACUGGUGAACGUGACAUUUUCACGAAGCCACAGCCCAUGGUCACUCCCUGCAAAGCUCUGAACUUGCGCAUUCCCAGGCCAGGCCGUGGUUGUCUUUCCAAGGCGGCUCAGCUUGUGCUUUGCUUGGAGAGAGCGGAGGGCAGCAGCACAGUGACAGCGUCUGGGACCUCAGACCAGUUUCCACAGCCACUUAUGAAAGCAGACGGCUCCAUGGGCUGGAGGAGGUGGGACGCUCUGGAAAGAACUCGGGUGCGAGUGGGAAAGAAAAUCGAGCUGAGCAGCUGGAAGUCGAAGUCGCGUGAGUGAGGACCAGACACUCUCGAUUUAGGCAAAGGCGGGGUGCACUUCCCAACAACACAUCCUCCUCACUGGCGAGACCAGGCCUGCCCUUCAAGUUCCUCUCCUGAUUUAAUCCCCUUGGCGAGGGUUUGGCAUGAAAUCAAUGGCCAGCAAGCUUGGUAAACGAAGCCGCCUACACCGCCCUCCCCCUCCCUGCACGGCCGCGCCCCGCCUCCGCUCCUGUCUCAAUCUGGGAUUGUCCUCCUGUAGCCCCACCAUCCACCGUGGGGAACGGUGGAGAGACUACAACUCCCAGUAUGCACCGCGAUGCGCGCCUCACCCUGCAUCUCCCAGCCCGCAGCCAGCUGGCAUCCUAGACCCUCUGCCCUGCGACCAACAGCCGGGAGCGGACCAGACACCAGAACUCCCGGAACGGUUGAAGACGGUUCCGCUCCCUGUCCCGCCUUUCGCAGCCCAGCAGUUUCGCCCUGCGGAGAGGAGCCUUGCUGUUUCCAAAUCUCUCCUGCUGAAGAGACAUUGGAGCUAGGGCGGCUAGUUUCACCUGGCUGUCACAAAUCCUCUGCACCCCAGGAGCGCCGCUUGGACCCCCGGGCUCGCUGCGUGGUCCAUAUCUAGGUCGGGCCUCUCACGGAGACUUUCCCACCAGUGUAAUAAAGAGGAGAAAACGUCACAGCGGAAGGGCCUGACCCUGCUGCAUCCACUAAGGAAACAGCUACGGGGAUGGGACCCUGGGAGCUGCUGUGGAGCCUCAUCCACCGCUUCUCUGACCCCACCCAGGCUGCUUCCCAGGCCUCAGGGUCUUAGUGUGGACCUCCGGGCCGUGAUUAAUGCA